GUCACGGAUUGGUCGCGGCCGCGAGCGCAGUGGUGUGGAGCGCGCCGGGUCCCGGAGCCGGCUGUCUGAGGGAUGGACGAGACGAGCCCACUAGUGUCCCCCGAGCGGGCCCAACCCCCGGACUACACCUUCCCGUCGGGCUCGGGCGCUCACUUUCCGCAGGUGCCCGGGGGCGCGGUCCGAGUGGCGGCGGCGGCCGGCUCGGGCCCCUCUCCGCCGGGCUCGCCGGGCCACGACCGCGAGCGGCAGCCACUGUUGGAUCGGGCCCGGGGCGCGGCGGCCCAGGGCCAGACCCAAACCGUGGCGGCGCAGGCCCAGGCUCUGGCCGCUCAGGCCGCGGCGGCAGCCCACGCCGCUCAGGCCCACCGCGAGCGGAACGAGUUCCCGGAGGAUCCUGAGUUCGAGGCGGUGGUGCGGCAGGCCGAGCUGGCCAUCGAGCGCUGCAUCUUUCCCGAGCGCAUCUACCAGGGCUCCAGCGGAAGCUACUUCGUCAAGGACCCUCAGGGGAGGAUCAUUGCUGUCUUCAAACCCAAGAAUGAAGAGCCCUAUGGGCAUCUUAAUCCUAAGUGGACCAAGUGGCUGCAGAAGCUGUGCUGUCCUUGCUGCUUUGGCCGUGACUGCCUUGUCCUUAACCAGGGCUAUCUCUCAGAAGCAGGGGCCAGCCUGGUGGACCAAAAACUGGAACUCAACAUUGUUCCCCGUACAAAGGUAGUAUACCUGGCCAGUGAGACCUUCAACUAUAGUGCCAUUGACCGAGUGAAGUCCAGGGGCAAGCGGCUUGCACUAGAGAAAGUGCCAAAAGUUGGACAGCGGUUUAACCGCAUCGGGCUACCACCAAAGGUUGGUUCAUUCCAGCUCUUUGUUGAAGGCUACAAAGAUGCAGACUAUUGGCUGCGGCGUUUUGAAGCAGAACCUCUUCCUGAGAACACUAACCGGCAACUACUGCUCCAGUUUGAGCGGUUGGUGGUGCUGGAUUACAUCAUCCGCAACACUGAUCGAGGCAAUGACAACUGGCUGAUUAAAUAUGACUGUCCAAUGGAUAGUUCUAGCUCUCGGGACACAGACUGGGUGGUGGUGAAGGAGCCUGUUAUCAAGGUGGCUGCCAUAGACAAUGGGCUGGCCUUCCCACUGAAGCAUCCUGACUCCUGGAGGGCAUAUCCUUUUUACUGGGCCUGGUUGCCCCAGGCGAAAGUCCCAUUUUCUCAGGAGAUCAAAGAUCUGAUCCUUCCAAAGAUAUCGGACCCUAACUUCGUCAAGGACUUGGAAGAGGACCUAUAUGAACUCUUCAAGAAAGAUCCUGGUUUCGACAGGGGCCAGUUCCAUAAGCAGAUUGCUGUCAUGCGGGGCCAGAUCUUAAAUCUGACCCAGGCCUUGAAAGACAACAAGAGUCCCCUGCACCUCGUCCAGAUGCCACCUGUGAUUGUCGAGACGGCCCGUUCCCACCAGCGGUCUUCUAGCGAGUCCUACACACAGAGCUUUCAGAGCCGGAAGCCCUUCUUUUCAUGGUGGUAGCUCCAGAGGCAGGCAGAGGAAAUAUUGUCAGAGACUGGUGGGAGGAAGCCUGGGGAGUGGGGUGCAGGAAAAGCCAGAGAAGCCGGUGGAGAGCAGCACCUUUAAGAGCCCUCUCUCUCUGCUUGCCACCCUGCUCAGAGCUUUCCACCCACAGGGAGAAGCACAAUCAGGAACAGUGAGUGCUCCUCGCCCUUCUGAUGUGGGGGAGGCUGGAGCUCCAUGCACGUAGUCCAGAUGCCUGGGAAGGAACAUCUCCCUUCCAGCAUCUGCUGGUAGCAGGCUGGGACAGUCCCUUCCUUCCCUGAAACCCUGCUCUAUUGCAAUUCCCUAUUAUAUUCUGCAUCAGAAAAACAAACAAAACAAAAACAACUUUAAAUGCUUGUAGCAGAACCCCGGGUCAUCUCAUGUCAGAAACCUUUAAUCCAGGCCUAAAUUUGCAUAGACCUGACAUUCAGCUGCCUUGCAGUUGCUUCCUCCCAUGAGCCAAGGUGGUGUCAGAGGGCAACUGGAUGACUCGCAGUACCACAGCACUGGGACAGACAGAAGCCACACCUUUCUUUUGGGUUUUUGCCAAGCCUCCUCCAUCUCCCAUCAGUGCUGUGGGCUGGCUGCAAGCCUCGAAACAGUUCUCCUGGAAGGGAGGUUUUUGCUUUACCCCCGCCAGCACUUCCGCACACAAUCAUAGAGAACCUCUCUGCUCUCUGCUGGCCUACAGCUUGUCUGUUUCUCAAGCAGAGGCAGGAAGAGCUAGUCUUAGCAUUUAUAUUUUAAUAGGAAGUUGACUCCCAGCAUGUAAAAGUGAUCCACGCAGCCGGAGUGUAUGCCGGGAGCUAAGUGGUCUAUGGGUGAACAUAUCCCACCUUGCUUCCUGAGUCCUUGGUCCCAAUCUUCUCAUUUGUUCCUCUCGUUUUAAAUUUUUUCCCCCCAACUCUUUUGAUGUAAGAGUUCAGUUUGUCUUCGGGAGUGGGUCUCUGCAAGGGCUCUGGGAUGAGUCUUGGCUUCCAAGAGGACAGGCUAUUAGGUUCUUGGACUUUUUUCUGUGCUACCGCUGCUGCUUGGUGGAAGUAACAGGACGUGGAUUCUGCCUCAUAAGUGGCAGUUUCCCUUUUCUCUCUGACUUGUCCUAGGCCGAUUUCUCUAUGGCUUCCCUGAGAAAGGUGAGGCCCAAAGGAGAGAGGCCUUCAAACUGUCCCAGGUCCUGCGCAGCUCAGUGCGUAUCUUCUUGCUUCCAUGUGUCUUUUCCCCUGCUGCCUCACUCCCCACCCCCACUUGCCAGGUGUUUGAGCCAUUUCUACACCAAAGCAAAGUACGGCCUCAGGAGGGAGUAAAAAGGGUGCCAUCUGUGUCUGGAGGGGCAGCUGUGUUCAUGCCCUGUGCUACUGGACAUUUCACAAUUCUGGCACCUUGCGAUUGGUCAGUCAACCUCAGAAAGUAACUAUCUUGAAGGUUUGAAAAACAACCAAAGAAAGGGAGUGAGGACUAUGGCUGCAUGUCCUCUGCUUGCCCGGCUGCAGAGCAGAGAUGUGCAGCCCUCUGGUCAGCUGGUCCAGGCUGGUCCCCGCCGGUCCCCUUCCAGUCCAGCCACCAAGAGUCCACUUGUCCCGGGCUUCCACCUGGCUGACAGGAAGAAUUUCUGAGAGCUGGAUGUGCAUGCCCUGUGGACGAAGGUACAGCUCGCCUGCCUGCCCCAAUCCCAGCCCCGACAAUCACAUGCAGCUGACUCGGACACUGGCCUUGGGAACAAUGUUCGAGAGAACACUUGCCCCUUGACUGUAGGAGCCAGAAGGGGACCCAGGUGUGCAUAGCUCUCUGUAGACAUUUUUACCCAAACCUGUUGGUAAAGUGCCCAUCUGGUGCUCAAGAGAGCCUGGGGGUCUAACAGGGAGCCCGGCUGCCUCACCUGGCCACAGCCUCCACACCAGAUCUCCACAUUGUCUUGAUCCAGACCAGCUCUGUGAUCAGAAGGAAAUUGGGUCCAGUGUAGGAGAGAGCUGGUCCUGGGCCUGGCAGGCAAGAGUGUGGGCAUCCUUUCCUGGCCUUUCUCCACUCUCCCUCAAGCCUGUGCUCAGGUUGCCUUGAAUGUGGACUCUGGAAGAGCCAGGGGCCCAGAAUGCCGGGGGAGGCUUCUGAGUGGCACUCAUGGAACACCGUCCCUCUGCCAGCCAUAGGCCCUGCCUCCAGUGUCAGGGAAUGGAGGCUGGGCUGCGAGAGUGUUGCUGCCCCCUGUGUCAUUCUUCUAAUCCAAUGUAGAAAUUGUACGUAAUGUAUUUAAAUCAACGCAAAUGUAUGAAUAACAAAUACAGUUCUGACCUUUUUUGUCCAGUUUCUUUGGGGGAAGGAAGACAAAGAAGGUAGGAACGGAAUUUUGAGGGCAAAGAAACCUGUGUUUCCAUGGAAUUGCUGAGACGUGGCUCCUGGGGCUAUUUCUCCCUAAUAAAGGAUGAUCCAGGUCCUCAUUUCCAAAGUCCCAAUGCUCUGAAAACCAAAAGUAUUUUCAUAACCCAUUUGAAACCAAACCUGACCUGAACUUACACUGAUAGGAAGCUAUGGGUAAUUAUGAUGUGUUCCUUUUAGUGUGAUUCUUUGUUGCAGAAAUGUCAAUAUAUUUUAUGACAUGGUUCCCUACUAGGGAUUAUACAGUAUUUGCUGACUACUUCCUAAGAGCCAAAAAUAAAAAAUCUGAAUUCCAAAA